CGGAACUGCAAGUCAAUUAAGCCUGUUUCCUUUAUAAAUUACCCAAUCUCAGGUAUUUCUUUACAUCAGUGUGAAAACAAAUGAAUACAGUCCCCUUCCCUGAGGUGCCUUCUCCUUAGGCAACCAGCUGCCCCCAUGCUCCUCUUCUGCCCCCCUGGUAUUUCCUUUCCCCUCAUGAGGCCCAAGUGAUCCACAUGGCCAGCCACAGCCCCAUCCUACUGCAGGCCUGUGUGGCUGCUAGAGAGGCCAGGCUCCUUUCCGCACCCCGAGGCUGCCCGAUAUGCUUUCUGCAUCCUGUAGAAAACUGACCCACUAUUCUCAUACUGGUGCAACUUCUUCCAUUACCUCAAAACUGGACAACGUGAACUUGUUUCUUGUCUCUUCUUGCUAGGGCUGUCACUGGGACAGUCCGAGAUGGGGGGGUGGGGGGAGACAAUGGAUGAAUGGAUGGAUGAAUGGACAGUAGUCCAGGGAGAUGUCCCUGUGUGUCCUGAACUGGGACCUUCCUCCAAUGAGAAGCCUUCCUGAGUGAGUUUAUACAGUCAUCCCUUGGUAUCCAUGGAUUAGUUCUAGGGUCCCCGGGGAUGCCAAAAUCCAUGGAUCCUCAAGUCUCUGACAUAACAUGGCCUAGUAUUUACAUAUCAGCUAUGCACAUCCUCCCGUAGACAUUAGACCAUCUCUGGAUUAUUCAUGAUGUGUAAUACAAUGCAGAUGCUACAUAAAUGGUCGUGAUACUGGAUUCUUUAGGGAAUAAUGACAAGAACAAACUCUGCACAUGUUCAAUAGAAACAUAACCGUCCAAUUUAUUUUCUGAAUAUUUUCCAUCUGCUGUUGCUGAAUCUACAGAUGCAGAGCUCCUGGAUACGAGAGCCAAGUGUGCUUUGAGAGUAGGGUGGGUGAGGUUGCUAAUGAGUACAGGGGAGCAGGUGUUGAUCAGGAGGACCCUGCACUGGGGCAUCUGGACGUCCUGCCUCAGGACUUGAGACUCCAGUUGGAUGGCACAGGCAGACUCAGCCCAGGUCAAAGCCGUCCCCUUGAAGUUUCUUUUUAUCCCAAGCUCUUUCUGGCCCCUGGAAUUUGGCAUCCCCUAGGCCCUGUGUGGAAGGACAGAUGAACCAGGUUUUAGAUAACAUGUCUAGAAGAGUGAGCCCCUAACUGUGUGCCCGGCACUUUCCCCACAGGAUCCUCUAGCUAGAAUAUCCAAGGGUCAUGGAGAGAAAUACCCAGUUAAAAUAUCAGAAAUGAAAAAGCGAUACCAUUAGAGACACUAAAAAGACCAUUAGGUAAUAGUACUAGCUUUUGUAUUCUGAGAUCCAACAGCAGCAGUCACUUCCCUCCACCGCUAUGUGUAUCCCAGGACCACCCUGGGCGGGGAGGGCUGAGGUUAGGGAGCAGCCAUGGAUGCUCUGAUGCUGGCCCUGGGCCUCGGGGGUGACAGUGAUGAGGAACUGGGUGCACACAUGAGUGGGGCAGCCGGGCCUGGCCAGAGAAGCAGCACACACGUGCACAGAUGUGUUUACCCACAUACACAUGUGCACGCACGUGCACAAACACAUUGCAGGCAGGCAUGUUGACGCCUCAGGCAGCGGAGGACCCUGACUCUGGGCGCUGCUGACCCGGGCAAGGCCCCACUGUGAUUCGUGCCAUGACCUCAGAAUGUCACUGGUGCUUAGCACCUAUCUGCUCUCUGGUCUGCCUCAGUGGUCUACAGCAGUUACACACAGGCAGUGGUAUCUGUGAGCAGCUCUGUGGACUCAAAGGUUUUCUCCCUGAGAGGCACGACCCAGGCCAGCUGAUUCAUCAGAAUCAGGUGAGCGUGACCUGCUCUCUUCCCUCCAGGCGGACUUGGGGGCAGUGGCUACGGUGCGGGCGGUGUUGGCCUCUGUGGGGCAGCUACCGAGGAGGGUCAUCCCUGAGCACUCACCAGGCGCCCGUUCUACACUGCCCGUGUAGACGAUUGGCUCUUUCGUCUCCAUGGUGGCUUCGUAGAGUGGGUGCUGUUCCCAAAUGUCCCCAUUCGACAGAUGAGACGUCUGGGGUCAGAGAGGCAGUAACCGGCCUGGGAAUCCGGACAUGACCCUGAGUUUUGCUCUCAGCCCUGCCGUGUGCUGUGCUGGAAUUCAGGCCUGAACCCUGUGACCUCCCUGCCCUAGAUCCCAAAUCUGCCCAGGUUUCCCAUCCCGAUGGGGCAGAGCCUGGUCCUGGCAGAGCCACUGGUAUAGAGCCACUGGUACAGAUCCACUGACGGUCCUCAGAACACCUCUGUGCCCUAAGCUGGGUCCUGAUGGUCGCUGUGGGCCCCACUGAACACACAUGGUCCCUUGUCCGGGGGAGCCUGCUGCCCUUGGGCAGCUGUGGAAAAUGAAGGAGCCCUGGAGGGCUGGCUGAGGGGAGACUAUCUUCCCUUGUGUUCAAAGGGGUCCGGGCACUAGGGUUCUCCCCAGGUAUUUCUUGCUCUGCGUGGUCCUCUUGAGGCCUCGCCCUCCUUUUGCCUCGAGUAUUCCCAGGAGGGACGGUCCAUCCAGCUGUUCUCCAGGACCAAGGACCCACUGUUCUUCCUCAGUGACCCAGGAAAAUGAAGCCUCCUCCUGUUGGGACGGCUCAGAAUGGUGGACUCCACAGUCCCUCCGCGAGAGACGUGGUUUCCAUGCGUACAAUAGAUCUUUCUCAUCCCCCAAACCCAACACCCUCCUGCUCAACAGGCGUUAUUCCUAAAGUGGCUUCACUGUUCAGACUGAAGAGCCACGGUAGCCAAAGUGAUGAGCGGAGUAGAACCGAGCAGUCGGGAGAGAUCUUGUUCCCUGUAGGAAACUGGGCAUCGCUGAGGCCCUGAGCAUCCCAGGAGGCCGAUUGCACAGAGACCUCUGGUCGCUGACCCCAGUCUGCCUCCACAUCCCUGGAAUAGCCCAUCAUGGGCCCUUCACCCUUGGCAGGUGGAAACCAUUCAACCUGCUGGGGCCGGUGUGUCCCCAUUUCAUGGCAUUGGGGGACAACAGGAUUCUCUGUCUAGGUCCCACUGUACUCAAGUCCUUGGGAAGAUGCCCACCCCUGCUUGGGACUUGAGACUCCAGAGACUGGAGCAGCUGUGGGCCACUGGGUCUGGCCCCUUUUUCCCUGGGGGCGGCGGUGGAAUGGGGGUUACGCAGCCAGCCAGCAUCUGGGAGCCCGGCGAGAGCGGUUCAGGUGUUCUCCGAAGCCGCCGCGUACGGUGUGACCUUUAGACAAUUCUGUCUCACAGGAUGGACGUGGUAGAGGUCGCGGGCAGUUGGUGGGCACAAGAGCGAGAGGACAUCAUUAUGAAAUACGAAAAGGGACACCGAGCUGGGCUGCCAGAGGACAAGGGGCCUAAGCCUUUUCGAAGCUACAACAACAACGUCGAUCAUUUGGGGAUUGUACAUGAGACGGAGCUGCCUCCUCUGACUGCGCGGGAGGCGAAGCAAAUUCGGCGGGAGAUCAGCCGAAAGAGCAAGUGGGUGGAUAUGCUGGGAGACUGGGAGAAAUACAAAAGCAGCAGAAAGCUCAUAGAUCGAGCGUACAAGGGAAUGCCCAUGAACAUCCGGGGCCCGAUGUGGUCAGUCCUCCUGAACACUGAGGAAAUGAAGUUGAAAAACCCCGGAAGAUACCAGAUCAUGAAGGAGAAGGGCAAGAGGUCAUCUGAGCACAUCCAGCGCAUCGACCGGGACGUAAGCGGGACAUUAAGGAAGCAUAUAUUCUUCAGGGAUCGAUACGGAACCAAGCAGCGGGAACUACUCCACAUCCUCCUGGCAUAUGAGGAGUAUAACCCGGAGGUGGGCUACUGCAGGGACCUGAGCCACAUCGCCGCCUUGUUCCUCCUCUAUCUUCCUGAGGAGGAUGCAUUCUGGGCACUGGUGCAGCUGCUGGCCAGUGAGAGGCACUCCCUGCAGGGAUUUCACAGCCCAAAUGGCGGGACCGUCCAGGGGCUCCAAGACCAACAGGAGCAUGUGGUAGCCACGUCACAACCCAAGACCAUGGGGCAUCAGGACAAGAAAGAUCUAUGUGGGCAGUGUUCCCCGUUAGGCUGCCUCAUCCGGAUAUUGAUUGACGGGAUCUCUCUCGGGCUCACCCUGCGCCUGUGGGACGUGUAUCUGGUAGAAGGCGAACAGGCGUUGAUGCCGAUAACAAGAAUCGCCUUUAAGGUUCAGCAGAAGCGCCUCACGAAGACGUCCAGGUGUGGCCCGUGGGCACGUUUUUGCAACCGGUUCGUUGAUACCUGGGCCAGGGAUGAGGACACUGUGCUCAAGCAUCUUAGGGCCUCUAUGAAGAAACUAACAAGAAAGCAGGGGGACCUGCCACCCCCAGCCAAACCCGAGCAAGGGUCGUCGGCAUCCAGGCCUGUGCCGGCUUCACGUGGCGGGAAGACCCUCUGCAAGGGGGACAGGCAGGCCCCUCCAGGCCCACCAGCCCGGUUCCCGCGGCCCAUUUGGUCAGCUUCCCCGCCACGGGCACCUCGUUCUUCCACACCCUGUCCUGGUGGGGCUGUCCGGGAAGACACCUACCCUGUGGGCACUCAGGGUGUGCCCAGCCCGGCCCUGGCUCAGGGAGGACCUCAGGGUUCCUGGAGAUUCCUGCAGUGGAACUCCAUGCCCCGCCUCCCAACGGACCUGGACGUAGAGGGCCCUUGGUUCCGCCAUUAUGAUUUCAGACAGAGCUGCUGGGUCCGUGCCAUAUCCCAGGAGGACCAGCUGGCCCCCUGCUGGCAGGCUGAACACCCUGCGGAGCGGGUGAGAUCGGCUUUCGCUGCACCCAGCACUGAUUCCGACCAGGGCACCCCCUUCAGAGCUAGGGACGAACAGCAGUGUGCUCCCACCUCAGGGCCUUGCCUCUGCGGCCUCCACUUGGAAAGUUCUCAGUUCCCUCCAGGCUUCUAGAAGCAUCUGGGCCAGGGCUCAUGGCUGGAUAAUUUCCCUAGGCUUAACAACCCAAGCAAGCUUCGCAUCCUCGUUUUAUUUUUGGUUAAACUUAUGAAAAUGUAUUAAGAAAGAGUGCAGCUCGAGAGAGAUUCAGAGAUGGAACACACCAGACCCCAGAUCACAAAGCCAACCAUGCCCGGCCCCUCCCAGCACCCCCAGCCCCACGACCAUCGUUCUGAAUUCUGACGACACCGUGAGCCUGCCUUUGUACUUCAAACUCAUGGAAGGAUAACCACCUUCAUGUUUUGAAAUAAAUGUUUCCUGUUGAAAUGA